ACAGUUGUUUCCGGGAAGCGGGACUCCAAAUGGGUCGCAGUCGCAGCCGCUCUCCACGGAGGGAACGUAGGCGUUCCCGGUCCACAUCCCGGGAGAGAGAACGCAGGCGCCGAGAAAGGUCCAGGUCUCGGGAGAGAGAUCGGAGAAGGAGCCGCUCGCGAUCCCCGCACCGAAGACGCUCCCGAUCUCCAAGACGACAUAGAUCCACAUCUCCUUCCCCUUCUCGACUGAAAGAAAGAAGAGAUGAGGAAAAGAAAGAAACAAAAGAAACAAAGAGCAAAGAACGGCAGAUUACUGAGGAAGACUUAGAGGGCAAAACAGAGGAAGAAAUAGAAAUGAUGAAGUUAAUGGGAUUUGCCUCCUUUGACUCCACAAAAGGUAAGAAGGUGGAUGGCUCUGUAAAUGCCUAUGCCAUAAAUGUCUCUCAGAAGAGGAAGUACAGGCAGUACAUGAAUCGAAAAGGUGGAUUCAACAGACCUUUGGAUUUCAUUGCAUGAGAAUUGAAGUGUUGAAGGAUGAUUUUUUUUCCCCUCAUCUUGGUCAGAGAGUGGAUUUUGUAUUUUGUAUUUAACUUGCAUUCAAAAAACAGGAUCUCAGUUCUCCUUUCUUGUAAAGUAAGAAAAUCUUAUUUAUGAUAUAUGCAGUUAACUUACCUUGCCUCAACAGAAGAAAGGUUAAAUAUUACAUUUUUUUCUUUUAGGAAAUAUCAUUUGUGGCAGGCGUCAACCCCAUUUUAUUUGUCCUUAUUCCUGUGGAAGCAGUAUAUGUUUUCUUCCUGAAUGCUCAUUAGGACUUCUUAAAAAACAUGAAAGUAAUUUGGAAGUAAGUUUAUCCAAUAAAGCAGUAUUUCUACCCUUUUAGAUUUGAUAAAUAUUUUUAUUACUAAAGAAUCUCCCCAGACAUUUUCUUUUUUUUUUCACACAUAGAUUUAAGUAUCUUGAUUGUUAGUAGUCUAAAAAUGGGAAGAAUGAAAAAGCAUAACUAGAUUUUUCUAUCUUCUGUGGUCGCCCGCCCCCCCCCAAAAAAAUACCAUUUAUGGUUCUCUCCGCAAGUAUAAAAGCAUUACAUGCAAAAAAAAGAUCUCAGAGAAAACAAAAGUAAAAGAAAAGCAGAAAAUCACCUGUUAUCUACUCCCAGAAAUAAUCAAUUUCAACAUUUUGGUAUAUGUUUUUCCAGGCUUCUUUGGGUUGAUCCCACCUAUGAGAUCAGAAUAUGUAUGCAGUUCUUUCUUUAACCCUUUUUUCUCCUAUGUACUGUGAACAUUUAAAAAGUACUUUUAAAUAUUCUUUGGAAACUUAGCUUUUAGUAACUACUUGGUUGUAUCAUAAUUUAUUAACUAAUGUUUUAUUGGUAAACAUUGGCUUGCCUCCCAUGACUUGCCAUUAUAAUUAAAACUGUGACUACUAUCUGUCUCCAUUACAUACA